AGUAGUUGACAUUUACAAGGAGCAGCGCCCCCAAAGGUCUUUAGCUGUUUUUUAAGGGGAGAACAGCCUUUACCCUCUUUGGACUUUUUCUUCGUUUUUUUUUUUUUUGGAGACGGAGUUUCGUUCUUUCGCCCAGGCUGGCGUACAGUGGCGCGAUCUCGGCUCACUGCAACCUCUGCUCCCCGGGUUCAAGCGAUUCUCCUGCCUCAGCCUCCCGAGUAGCUGGGAUUACAGGUGCCCGCCACCACGCCCGGCUGAUUUCCUCUUAAGACUUUCUACAGCUUCCUUAUGAAAUCUUCUGACUGGGCCUUGAGCAAUAAGGUCUUUUGCUACAAUUUAGUGCUCUUUUCCUCACACUAAAUCGAAAACUCUCCCUGUUGGUCCUGAUCUGUUUCAGUCAGGCAAAUUACAUCCUGGGAAAACGUCAGAUGACAGGGGAGGCCACUCGCUUCCUGCUCAUCCAGUUUCGACACUUUCUGUGCUUUCAUUAGCUUCCAGACCUCAGCCCUGGCCCUCGCUUUACUGUACAGUCAGAACUGGUUUCUACGCCUCGCGAGGGUGGGAGGUCGUGUAUGGGAGGAGGACCGCUUCCCACCAGCCUCGUUGGGAAGCCAGGAGAAAUCUCUUCAAAUCCUGCGAUUCAGAGUCAAGUCCCAGUCGUCCUUUUUCUGGUCGGCCCAGAACUGUUUGUGCCUCCUCCCUCAUGAGGAAUGAUGUCAGUGGGGCCGCGGUCGCCGCCCACGAAGAGUGUUGUUAAAAAAGCAGACAUGAUCAACAAAAAUAUGACUCAUCAGGUCCAAGCUGAGAGAGAUGCACUGGCACUAAGCAAAAGCCCAUUCAUUGUCCAUUUGUAUUAUUCACUGCAGUCUGCAAACAAUGUCUACUUGGUAAUGGAAUAUCUUAUUGGGGGAGAUGUCAAGUCUCUCCUACAUAUAUAUGGUUAUUUUGAUGAAGAGAUGGCUGUGAAAUAUAUUUCUGAAGUAGCACUGGCUCUAGACUACCUUCACAGACAUGGAAUCAUCCACAGGGACUUGAAACCGGACAAUAUGCUUAUUUCUAAUGAGGGUCAUAUUAAACUGACGGAUUUUGGCCUUUCAAAAGUUACUUUGAAUAGAGAUAUUAAUAUGAUGGAUAUCCUUACAACACCAUCAAUGGCAAAACCUAGACAAGAUUAUUCAAGAACCCCAGGACAAGUGUUAUCGCUUAUCAGCUCGUUGGGAUUUAACACACCAAUUGCAGAAAAAAAUCAAGACCCUGCAAACAUCCUUUCAGCCUGUCUGUCUGAAACAUCACAGCUUUCUCAAGGACUCGUAUGCCCUAUGUCUGUAGAUCAAAAGGACACUACGCCUUAUUCUAGCAAAUUACUAAAAUCAUGUCUUGAAACAGUUGCCUCCAACCCAGGAAUGCCUGUGAAGUGUCUAACUUCUAAUUUACUCCAGUCUAGGAAAAGGCUGGCCACAUCCAGUGCCAGUAGUCAAUCCCACACCUUCAUAUCCAGUGUGGAAUCAGAAUGCCACAGCAGUCCCAAAUGGGAAAAAGAUUGCCAGGAAAGUGAUGAAGCAUUGGGCCCAACAAUGAUGAGUUGGAAUGCAGUUGAAAAGUUAUGCGCAAAAUCUGCAAAUGCCAUUGAGACGAAAGGUUUCAAUAAAAAGGAUCUGGAGUUAGCUCUUUCUCCCAUUCAUAACAGCAGUGCCCUUCCCACCACUGGACGCUCUUGUGUAAACCUUGCUAAAAAAUGCUUCUCUGGGGAAGUUUCUUGGGAAGCAGUAGAACUGGAUGUAAAUAAUAUAAAUAUGGACACUGACACAAGUCAGUUAGGUUUCCAUCAGUCAAAUCAGUGGGCUGUGGAUUCUGGUGGGAUAUCUGAAGAGCACCUUGGGAAAAGAAGUUUAAAAAGAAAUUUUGAGUUGGUUGACUCCAGUCCUUGUAAAAAAAUUAUACAGAAUAAAAAAACUUGUGUAGAGUAUAAGCAUAACGAAAUGACAAAUUGUUAUACAAAUCAAAAUACAGGCUUAACAGUUGAAGUGCAGGACCUUAAGCUAUCAGUGCACAAAAGUCAACAAAAUGACUGUGCUAAUAAGGAGAACAUUGUCAAUUCUUUUACUGAUAAACAACAAACACCAGAAAAAUUACCUAUACCAAUGAUAGCAAAAAACCUUAUGUGUGAACUCGAUGAAGACUGUGAAAAGAAUAGUAAGAGGGACUACUUAAGUUCUAGUUUUCUAUGUUCUGAUGAUGAUAGAGCUUCUAAAAAUAUUUCUAUGAACUCUGAUUCAUCUUUUCCUGGAAUUUCUAUAAUGGAAAGUCCAUUAGAAAGUCAGCCCUUAGAUUCAGAUAGAAGCAUCAAAGAAUCCUCUUUUGAAGAAUCAAAUAUUGAAGAUCCACUUAUUGUAACACCAGAUUGCCAAGAAAAGACCUCACCAAAAGGUGUCGAGAACCCUGCUGUACAAGAGAGUAACCAAAAAAUGUUAGGUCCUCCUUUGGAGGUGCUGAAAACGUUAGCCUCUAAAAGAAAUGCUGUUGCUUUUCGAAGUUUUAACAGUCAUAUUAAUGCAUCCAAUAACUCAGAACCAUCCAGAAUGAACAUGACUUCUUUAGAUGCAAUGGAUAUUUCGUGUGCCUACAGUGGUUCAUAUCCCAUGGCUAUAACCCCUACUCAAAAAAGAAGAUCCUGUAUGCCACAUCAGCAGACCCCAAAUCAGAUCAAGUCGGGAACUCCAUACCGAACUCCGAAGAGUGUGAGAAGAGGGGUGGCCCCCGUUGAUGAUGGGCGAAUUCUAGGAACCCCAGACUACCUUGCACCUGAGCUGUUACUAGGCAGGGCCCAUGGAUUUCUGACUUCCGGUCCUGCGGUAGACUGGUGGGCACUUGGAGUUUGCUUGUUUGAAUUUCUAACAGGAAUUCCCCCUUUCAAUGAUGAAACACCACAACAAGUAUUCCAGAAUAUUCUGAAAAGAGAUAUCCCUUGGCCAGAAGGUGAAGAAAAGUUAUCUGAUAAUGCUCAAAGUGCAGUAGAAAUACUUUUAACCAUUGAUGAUACAAAGAGAGCUGGAAUGAAAGAGCUAAAACGUCAUCCUCUCUUCAGUGAUGUGGACUGGGAAAAUCUGCAGCAUCAGACUAUGCCUUUCAUCCCCCAGCCAGAUGAUGAAACAGAUACCUCCUAUUUUGAAGCCAGGAAUACUGCUCAGCACCUGACUGUAUCUGGAUUUAGUCUGUAGCACAAAAAUUUUCCUUUUAGUCUAGCCUUGUGUUAUAGAAUGAACUUGCAUAAUUAUAUACUCCUUAAUACUAGAUUGAUCUAAGGGGGAAAGAUCAUUAUUUAACCUAGUUCAAUGUGCUUUUAAUGUACGUUACAGCUUUCACAGAGUUAAAAGGCUGAAAGGAAUAUAGUCAGUAAUUUAUCUUAACCUCAAAACUGUAUAUAAAUCUUCAAAGCUUUUUUCAUUUAUUUAUUUUGUUUAUUGCACUUUAUGAAAACUGAAGCAUCAAUAAAAUUAGAGGACACUAUUGAGAGUGAGCCACUAGCUUGAUUUUCUUUCUCCUCUGAUUUCAGUUCACUGUUCAGUUUAGCAUUAAAAUAAUAAAAUAAUCAUACAGUUCCAUUUGAUUGUAAUUUACUUGCAUAUGAUUACCUUCAAAAGCUGUGUUCUUGAGGGCAAUCAUUUAAGGCCAUACUUGUGACCUCAGAAAUGCAGCUGGAAGGCCGGGCGCAGUGGCUCACGCAUGUAAUCCCAGCACUGUGGGAGGCCGAGGCAGGCUGAUCUUGAGGUCAGGAGUUCAAGACCAUCCUGGCCAACAUAAUGAAACCCCAUCUCUACUGUAAAUACACAAAUUAGCCGGGCAUGUUGGUGGGCGCCUGUAGUCCCAGCUACUCUGGAGGCUGAGGCAGGAGAAUCGCUGGAACCCAGGAGGAGGAGGUUGUGGUGAGCCAAGAUCGUGCCACUGCACUCCAGCCUGGGCAACAGAACAAGACUCCGUCUCAAAAAAAUAAAGGCAGCUGGAAAAUUCCUUCACUUAGUAACUCCUUUGGGGAAUAAGGAAUAAACAAAAAGACUAAGGCUUUCACUUACUUUACUAAUGAUACGGUUUUGCCACCUUAAUUUCUAUUGGUGCGUAGUCCACAAUAUGUAUUUGUUUAAAAUGGUACUGGAGGACGGGUGCGAUGGCUCAUGCCUGUAAUCCCGGCACUUUGGGAGGCUGAGGCAGGCAAGUCGCUUGAGGCCUGGAGUUUGAGACCAGCCUGGCCAACAUGGCAAAACCUGGUCUCUACUAAAAAUAGAAAAAUUAGCCAGGUAUGGUGACGCACACCUGUAGUCCCAGCUACUUGGGAGGCUGAGGCAUGAGAAUCGCUUGAACCCAGGAGGUGGAGAUUGCAGUGAGCUGAGAUCACAUCACUGCAUUUCAGCCUGGGCAACAGAAUGAGACUCAGUCUCAAAAAAAAAAAAAAUACUACUGGAACAAUUAGGUGUGAUAUAAUGUAGCAAUUUGAAUAGCUUGUUCAAUUUUAAUAGAAAAUGUGAUGCUUUACAUCUUAUUGUCAUUUAUUUAAAACAUGCAACAUUAUCAGAAACAGAUUGGUCCUUAAAAAACAAAACAUAAUUUUCUUUUGCUUAAUAAAUAUAACUAUCACAAGUA